GCACUGGCCAGGGGUUCCGGCUGUAUAUCCAUGAGCGCCGCUGGCAGCCGGGGAGCUGCAGGAACCAGACUGGGGGCGAGCUGAGCACCUGUAGUCAAUCACACGCAGGCACAGAUGAAUCCUUCAUAUUUAUCUGGAUUUAGCUGGUAGCAUUUGUCUCCUAAGACUUGGUCACAGAGGAAUCCAUGUGACCUUCAGGCCUUCUGCUCUAAACUGGCAGGAGAUCCUGUUUCUACUCACAGCGUCCGAGGGUCUGGUGGCCGAGCCCUGAGGGGCGCUGUUGCUCCCAGGUGGCAGAAUUCAGCAUCAGAGAGCCACACAGCUGAAAGAGAUGGAUGGGUGAGUGACCUCAGCUUUGCCCAGCUGGGGUGAGUGGGCCGAGCAAGUCUCUCCUUUGGCAAAAUCAUCUGGGCUUGUUCUCAUCCCUGCUGAAUUGGCAGGGGAGGAGAGGGUCGUGGCCCAUUGGUCAUUGGUCGGGUUUCCUCACAAAUGCCUGCCAUGGUGAAAUGCAAGACUGUUAGAGUGAUAAUGGGCUGCACGUGUUAAUGCUGUCAUCACGGGCCCCACAGUGUGUAUUAGCCAAGUACUGGGGGCACUGGGAGCCUUGUCUGCUCCCAGUCGGCGUUGGGAAACCAGAACGCUCAGGAACGCUUUUAGGUUUGUUUGAAUAAGAGAUCUGACCUGACCGGCCCAACUGUACAACUCUUCAAGGAAAAUUCGUAUUUGCAGUGGGAAGAAUAAGUAACAUUGAUCAAGAUGAAUGCCAUGCUGGAGACUCCCGAACUCCCAGCCGUGUUUGAUGGAGUGAAGCUGGCUGCAGUGGCUGCUGUGCUGUACGUGAUCGUCCGGUGUUUGAACCUGAAGAGCCCCACAGCCCCACCUGACCUCUACUUCCAGGACUCGGGGCUCUCACGCUUUCUGCUCAAGUCCUGUCCUCUUCUGACCAAAGAAUACAUUCCACCGUUGAUCUGGGGGAAAAGUGGACACAUCCAGACAGCCUUGUAUGGGAAGAUGGGAAGGGUGAGGUCGCCACAUCCUUAUGGGCACCGGAAGUUCAUCACUAUGUCUGAUGGAGCCACUUCUACAUUCGACCUCUUCGAGCCCUUGGCUGAGCACUGUGUUGGAGAUGAUAUCACCAUGGUCAUCUGCCCUGGAAUUGCCAAUCACAGCGAGAAGCAAUACAUCCGCACUUUCGUUGACUACGCCCAGAAAAAUGGCUAUCGGUGCGCCGUGCUGAACCACCUGGGUGCCCUGCCCAACAUUGAAUUGACCUCGCCACGCAUGUUCACCUAUGGCUGCACGUGGGAAUUUGGAGCCAUGGUGAACUACAUCAAGAAGACAUAUCCCCUGACCCAGCUGGUCGUCGUGGGCUUCAGCCUGGGUGGUAACAUUGUGUGCAAAUACUUGGGGGAGACUCAGGCAAACCAAGAGAAGGUCCUGUGCUGCGUCAGCGUGUGCCAGGGGUACAGUGCACUGAGGGCCCAGGAAACCUUCAUGCAAUGGGAUCAGUGCCGGCGGUUCUACAACUUCCUCAUGGCUGACAACAUGAAGAAGAUCAUCCUCUCGCACAGGCAAGCUCUUUUUGGAGACCAUGUUAAGAAACCCCAGAGCCUGGAAGACACGGACUUGAGCCGGCUCUACACAGCAACAUCCCUGAUGCAGAUUGAUGACAAUGUGAUGAGGAAGUUUCACGGCUAUAACUCCCUGAAGGAAUACUAUGAGGAAGAAAGUUGCAUGCGGUACCUGCACAGGAUUUAUGUUCCUCUCAUGCUGGUUAAUGCAGCUGACGAUCCGUUGGUGCAUGAAAGUCUUCUAACCAUUCCAAAAUCUCUUUCAGAGAAACGAGAGAACGUCAUGUUUGUGCUGCCUCUGCAUGGGGGCCACUUGGGCUUCUUUGAGGGCUCUGUGCUGUUCCCCGAGCCCCUGACAUGGAUGGAUAAGCUGGUGGUGGAGUACGCCAACGCCAUUUGCCAAUGGGAGCGUAACAAGUUGCAGUGCUCUGACACGGAGCAGGUGGAGGCCGACCUGGAGUGAGGCCUCCGGACUCUGGCACGCUCCAGCAGCCCUCCUCUGGAAGCUGCGUCCCCUCACCCCCUGUUUCAGGUCUCCCAUCUCCCUCAGUGACCUGGAUCUGACCUCACACCAUCAGCAGGGGGCACCCACCAUGCACACCUGUCUCGGAGUAGGCAGCUCUUCCUGGGAGCUCCAGGCUAUUUUUGUGCUUAGUUACUGGUUUUCUCCAUUGCAUUGUUAGGCAUGGUGACAAGUGACAGAGUUCUUGCCCUCUGUCCAGUUUCAGCAUCUGGUUGCUUUUAAGCCAAGUACAUCUAGUUUCCCUAUUAAAAAUGUGUCUGAAUAGCGAUUUUGCUUUGCCACCAAAAGGCUUUUCCCUGAGAACAGUGAAGGAUGUAUGUCAUUUUGUGGUGGUUGUAUGUGUCCUUACAUAGACCUUAAAAAGAGCUCACCCUUCCAGGCCAAUGCUGAAGACACAGCUCCGCUUGGGAGCCUGAGAACCCAGGCUUCCCAGGCCAGAGUGUGGCUUCUUAAACGGCAAAGGAAAUUCCUUUGAGUCACAAGCCAAGUUUUCGCCCUGUCUCCUGAGACCAUUUCCCUACGCUUUGCUGCUGCUGAGAGUUACGUGAGGCACUUGUUAAAAAUUCAGCCUCCCAGGUCCCUCCCCUCGGAGAGGCUGAUUCACUGGGUCUGGGAAGGAGCCUGGGGAUUUUAAUUUUUCACAAGUGCCCCAGAUGAUUCUCAUCACCAAGCAAAUUUUGGAAAUGCUGUUCAACAGCGCCCUUAAAUUGGAAACAUCUUUGCAGCUCGUUUUAUUGAAAUUCAUAAUCAGGGGUGUCCUCUAGCUCCCACGGUCUCCAGAGCAGCAAGGCCGGCUAUGGAGCUGCCGUCGUGUGACCACAGUGUGAUGUCUCAGAAGGGCUCUGGGUGGGCUGAGCAUCUGGGCUGUGCCCUGGCUCUGCUUUUCACCCUGGACAAAGUCGCUGUGGACUUCAAUUUCUUCACCUCUAAAAUGGGGGACUUGGACCAGGUAGAUUGCUGAGCUCACUACCAGGUUCAAAGUUCAAUGACAAACUCAGUUUACUGAGGUUUGAGAGAACAUCCCUCCAGGGGAGCCUGGGAGCUGCUCUCCCAGUCUAAGCAUGUAGAUAUCAUCGUUUGCCUUUUGUGUGUGUGUGUCCCUUAUUUGAUAAAAAGAUGUUUUGAGUUGUUUUUUUUUUAAGCACUCACUUGUAAUUUUAGUUUUUAAACCCAAGUCCCUCUAACUUUGCCUUUGAUACCAAACAAUUCAAAAGUUGGAUCUGAGUUUGGAGAAAGAUAUUUCCAACCUAAGUGGGUAUUAUUUUGAAACCAGAUUUUUAAUUUAAUAGCCUAUAUUUGUAGUCUGUUGGAUAGGUGUUUCCAAAGUGUGUCUUCUCAAGUGAAAACGCAACUCUAGGUUUCAAGUACUCCUUUUCUCCGAUCCUGUGGUACUUGAAUAUCCAAAAACCCUGCACUUUGAACAAUCAGCUGUUGCUAUCUGGAACUAAACAGAACUAUGAGUAAAAUUGCCUGGAUACUUUAAAAAGAUAUUUUUCCUCCUUCAUCUCCUUUGACUCCAGGACAGACUGGAAUAUAAGUAGUGGGUCUGCAUGGAUGUUUCAGGGAUCAAAGGAGCCACCUGGGCGCCUGAGUGCCAACCCUCAGGGCCACAGGUGGGUGUGGUUUGGGCACGGGUCCAAGUGACUGUGACGGGACCCGUGGGCAUGGGUCCAGGUCUGUAACCUGAAGAAGUUGUUUUCUGACAAUCACCAAAUCAUCCGAAUGACAUCAAAAGCAGCCCUUAUCUCAGAGACUGAGAUUUCUGUGGUCUCAACUUCGCUUUGGUAUAAUUUCUGGCACUCACCAGCCUCUAUCAUUAUGACUUUCCCCCCAGUGUAUUAUUUCUCUAAUAGGUUUCCUUUUCACGUUCUUUUAGCACAGACUGGCACUUUACCCUCUCAGUUUGGAAGUUAGCCCCUCUCCUCUGUUACUUUUCCCUUCACCCAACUACAGCUGUGAUCUAGAACAUUCAUAGUCAUAUUUCUGCUACUACUACCUUCAUUUAUCAAGACUUUUUAUGAGAAUAGGUAAACCAAGCAAUAACUUCCUAGGACUGAAUCACCACCCCAGAAGAGCGAGAGGCUCCUUUCAUAUGCCUGAGGCCACACCCCUUAACCUGUUCUGACAAAAUAGUGGCUGGCCCAUGUACCAGCUCCAUUCAGAAAUUCAGGAAGAGAAAAGACAGCCCUGUUGUCACACAAACCGGUGUGGGGGAGGGUGGAGCCUGGUCUGCACGGCAGUCCUGGUGGCCCCUGUGGAGGACAGGCAGGGCUGGCAGCAUAGCCUUUGUUGCCACACAACCGGAAUUUGCUCCCCCAGGACUGUGGGAGCCAGUGUCCCAGCUGAAAUCUUUUUAGUGUGUGGCUCUGAAUGGCACUCACAUUCCAUUUUGGCUCACAUGAAACUAACUGAAGCCCUUUGUUCAAGCUUCAGGCUCUUAGGCAUGGAAAUGAGAAUGUGACUGUGGCUGUCUUACAGGAAAAUUCUUGUUUGUCCCUGAAUGAGAGCACAGAGGCAUUGAAUUCACAGAGCUGCAAACUUGCCUGAUAAAUGAGGGAGUGGCAGUUUAUAGAUAGGUCAUCUUUUUUCCUUCCUCCAGGUGUCCUUGCCUUUCUUCCCAAAGUCAUUCAUUUCUGAUGAGUAUAUGAAUCCCCCUCUUGCUAGUAAGGUUCUAUUUGGGCUAAAACAAGGCUGAAUUUUUAAAGAGUAUUUGAAUAUAUUUUAGAAUCAAAUUGAGGCUAUAAAUUGCAUCAAUCUGGACAAUUCCAUUGCAGGAAUAAUAUGUUAAAAACCAAUGGGGAGAAGCACCCACAUCUCUCCUGUAGCACUCCGUGUCUCAUAAGCAAUUUGAAGACACUUACAAGUAACUGAUUCCAGUCAAAUUAGGAUUAACUGACUCAAAAAAUGGUGUCAAGUUUCUUUAAUGUUUUUAUGUUAGAAGUGAGUUUAACAGACUUGAAGAAAACUGUUAUCUUUUCCUGCUGUGAGUUUACACAAAUGAUUCCAGAGCAGAAUGAAAGCAGAAAGCUGUUGGUUACAAUAUUCUUUUAACCUCUCUGCAGCAUUUUACACUUACUGGGAACCUUAUGAUUCACCGUAAGAGUGGAAAUAUACCUGAGUUCGUGUCCUAAUGGUCUCUAAUUCACAUUGGAUCGUGGGCAAAUCACCUCACCUCUCUGAGCCUGUUCCCUCCUCUUAGACCAUCUCUAAGACCACUUCAUCUAUUUACACAUCAUUUGCUUGAACAUUGCUGAACAUCUGCGUGAACUUGGCCUCUCCAGCCCUUGCAGGUGGAAACAGCUGUGUCAAGGCUCAAGGCUCACGCUGAGGGGACUUGGAGGGAGGGGGCUUCUGCAUUAAGCUUUCCUGGUGAAGACCCUUGAUCUUGUCCAAAGCCCUGUGUCUUUGACUGGCUUCUCUUCAGAGUCCCCGUUGUCAUCGUAAGACCCUUGCUGUUUGGAGGGUGGUCUUGUGACUGUGGCAGCUGCUGGCCGCUGGAAUGAGGAGCCUAUCUCCAUCCUCCAGUGUGACUCAGGCAGAGCAUUGAGAAUUCCCAGGGCAGAAAUCCUUCCUGCUCAGGCUUUCAUUCUAAAACUACAGUCUUCAUUAAAGCUGAACUUUCUGGGUAGCUGAGCUUAUAUGCCCGGCAUCUGAAUGAGAGCUCUCUUUGUAACUGUGUGACUUGAGAUCUAGUUUGCCAGCUCCUGGGAAACAAUACAUGUGUUCUUGUUUGUGUUUGCUCAGCAAGCAGAUGUCUGAGAUGUAAGAAGCUUUUCUUUUCCUGUGGCAUUGAUUCUGACUUAGAGCUGAAGUAAAAGAUCACUGAAACAUCACGUCAAGUUGAAGUCACUCAUAGGUCUUUGUCCUUUAGGCAGGACAGGAGAGUCAUUAAGAAGCAUUUCACUGUAGCAUUCUAUCACAAUAUCAUCUGGAAUUGUUUUCUUUGCCCAGAAAGCCUUAACUUGCCUCUAGAGAAUCCCUGGUAUUACAACGAUAUUGCGGCAUUAGAAUUCCAACUCUUCUGCUGUGGAAGUUUGAAGCGAAGCUGCAGCAAAACCAGAGAAUUUCCUCAAGUGGCCUGUAGGCUCCUUGUUAUCUUAUGCCCCCACCCCUCCCUCAACAAUAUGAGUGAUCCAGAACUGGCCCAAACACCUCAGCUCUGGUCCCUUUUUGCCCUUCUUGGCCUUACUCUGUUGUUCAAAGCCACUUUGGAUUGCUUGGAUGCUUCGAACAGCCAUGAAAAGUAGCCUGCCUGUGGCAUUUAGAGGCCAAGCAAUUGACAGAAAGGGUUUCUUCUACCUCUGUUAUCUAAGCAGAGGGAAGUAAACCUCUCACCGCCCCCCACCCCUCACUGCCCCCGAUUACCCUAGAAUUGCUUUCGCCAAAUUGUAGUUGAAGCUAAGGAAGGGGAAUCUGGCCCCUGCUGGGAGAGGGAACUGGAAUGCCACACAAGGCAAGGCCUGCUUCCUUCCUUCCCCUCUGCUGCUGCUGCCUCGGAACGCUGCAGCCCAGGCUUCCUCCCACAGUGGCCCUUGGAAGCAGGCCGCAGAGUAGACAGCUGCUCCUUUUGGAAGAGUCAGUCCCCUGUGUUUUCUGAACUGUUUUUCCUAGCAUGUAUGUGGGUAGAGCUUUCAUGCAUCUCUAGUAAUAAUAAGCUGAAAUUAGUUUUUUUUUUAAUUCUCCAAUUUAAAACUUUUAAUUAAAAAGUAAAUUUUAAUGUCGAAAAUGCAAACUUGGGGAGGGCAGAAAGAUCACACACAAGGCUGUCACUUCAUACUUGCAGGAUUGCACAGCAGCCGGGCAGAGGCGCUCCUCACUUCCCAGAUGGGGCGGCGGGCAGCAGAGACGCACCUCACUUCCUAGACAGUGCGGCAGCCAGGCACAGGCACACCUCACUUCCCAGACAGUUGGGCGGCCAGGCAAGCGCUCCUCACUUCCCAGAUGGGGCGGCUCCCGGGAAGCGGGGCUCCUCACUUCCCAGACAGGGUGGCCAGGCAGAGGUGCUCCUCACUUCCCAGAACAAUUCUUUAUGAAUUUGAUAAAGGACUGAAGUGCAACUGAAAGCUGCUAGUGAUGAUCUGGUAAUAUACAAUUUGUCCAGUAGCCAGUUUGUUUUUAUUGUGUUUUCUAACCAUAAGAGAUCAUUAAAGGCAAAGCCUGUAUGACGCUGUACACACACAAAAAAAUGGUCACCGCAGGCCAUACUACCAAUGAAAUGGUAGGUAAACAAAUCUUCUGGUCAAGAGAAAAAAAAAAGAAAUAGCACUCUGCAUGCUUUGCUCUACAAGACGAAUUUCCCUAGAAAGAAUCCAAUGAAGGCCGGGCAUAGUGGCUCACUCCUGUAAUCCCAGCACUUUGGAGGCCGAGGCGGGUAGAUCACCUGAGGUUAGGAGUUCAAGACCAGCCUGGCCAACAUGGUGAAACCCCUUCUCUACUAAAAAUGCAAAAAUUAGCUGGGUGUGGUGGCGGGCGCCUGUAAUCCCAGCUACUCGGGAGGCUGAGGUGGGAGAAUUGCUUGAACCCAGGAGACGGAGGUUGCAGUGAGCCGAGAUCACGCCUCUGCACUCCAGCCUGGGCAACAAGAGUGAGACUCCGUCUCCAAAAAAAGAAAAGGAAUCCAGUGAAAAUGGCUGCAAUUACAACAAGAAGUGAAGGAAGAAGACUGGUGACAUCUCUGAAGGAUGCAGUUGAGGUUGAUCCAGGUUUAUCCGAAUAUGCUACCUUUCUGAGCCUUAAACCUUCAUCUCUCAGGUGUUGAUUUGCUUCUGAUAGCUUCAUCAUUUCUCCCUGAAGUCUUUUACACUCUUCUGUUAGUUUCCUUGUUUCAGUAUCAUGAAGUGAAGCACUGUGUGGUUGUGGCGUGGGCCCGUCUUGCUUAGAUGCAUUCAGUGGGACAGCUUUGCUGGGUUCCAUGUCAUUCAAUUUAUCAUUUUCAUUGGGGAUCUCCAUUUGGAAUCCAUUAAUUCAUGAGGUUUUGCCUCAUUCCACACAGCUUCCAUAUCUGAAGUGUUUAGUGGAGCAAAAAUUGUACCAUAAACUUGUGUUUACUCUUUUCAUUCGGAUCAUAGUCAAAGGGCUGUAGCAUUACUGAAACAGUCACAGUUGACCCUGGGUCAAUAAUUCCACUGUUGGGCCUCACACAGUACCGGUGAGGCACGGUAGUCUUCACUUUGAAACACACUUUUCUAUCCGAUGGAUUUCGCAAUUUAAGAUUUGUAGUGACUACAUCUGUGAAGGGGCCUUUGAAUUUGAGGUCUAUGGGCGGGUCGAGGACCAGGAUCUGCUCGUGCUUCGCCGUGGCCCCGGAGGCAGACGCCAUUGGAGAGACAGCGCAGAGCAGGGGGCGGCUUGCUCGCUGGGGGCGGGGGACGAUGGCGAGAGGGGAGGGGGAGCGAGUUCGCAUCUCUCCUUUUCCUGGUUAGACUCUGUUCAACCACAUUCUUAUGUUGGCAGAUCUGCUUCCAGAUUGAUUUUUAGAGCACCAUCACUUUCACAUUCCUGAUUCUGAUUUUGUUUUGUUUUGUUUGGGUUUUCUGAAACUUAAAAUGCUGCCCCGAAAAUACUAUAUUUUUGAGUUUGUGUUCUGAAAGCCUCCGUGCUGCUGGAUCUUUGGGGGGAAAUACAGGAUCCUUCAGCACUGAGGUGUUUAAGAUUUGCAACUAGCAAUGCAAUUUUUUCUAAAUAUGGGGAUAUUUACCUUUAUUAAGAAAUUAUACUAAACAUUGAUGUCCUUGAUCAUUUUAUGUUCUCAUAUUACUUUUGAUUCUACUAUGAUUGUGUGGUGGUGAACAAAGAUCAUUACAAACAAAAACUGUAAUUUUGUUAUAUUUGAUUCAAUGGAAUUUACCUAAAAAAUAAAGACUAAAAAUGUG